UAAUAAUAUUUGUGUAAGUACAGGGAUAUGUUUCUUCAACUCCAAAGUAUGAGUUAAUGUGCAUAUGCCAACUCUAGAAAUAAAGUAUUAAGUCAAAACUCCCAAGAAAAUUUCCCCAAAAAGUUGCUAACAGACGUUAUUUUAUUUUAUUUAUUUAUUUUGAUACAGAGUCUCUCCCACUGUCACCCAGGCUGGAGUGGUGCAGUGGCAUCAUCUCGAUUCACUGUAGCCUCCGCCUCCCAGAUUCAAGCCAUUCUCGUGCCUCAGCCUCCCUUGUAGCUGGGAUUACAGUUGCCCACCACCACGCCUGGCUGAUUUUUGUAUUUUUAGUAGAGAUGAGGUUUCACCAUGUUGGCCACGCUGGUCUCGAACUCCUGACCUCAAGUGAUCUGCCCGCCUUGGCUUCCCAAAGUGCUGGGAUUACAGUUGUGAGCCACUGCACCUGGCCUUUAAUUUUAAUUUCUAAAACUAUGGAGUAAUACUACAUUGAGGGAACAGAAUUUUCUAUUCCUUCAUUUGUAUUAUUAUUAAAUACAGUCAUGCAUUGCAUAAUGACAGGAAUACAUUUUGAGAAAUGGAUCAAGUGAUUUUUUCAUUGUGUAAACAUCAUAGGGUAUAUUUACACAAACUAGAUGUUAUAGCCUACUAUACAGCUAGGCUAUAUUGUAUAGCCUGUUACUCUUCGGCCACAAAACUGUACAGUGUGUUACUGUAUUGAACACCAUAGGCAAUUGAGACACAACGGCAUUUGUGUAUCUAAAUAUAGAAAAGGUAAUGCAUUGUGCCACCAAAUCAACAACAGCUAUGAUGUCACUGGGUGAUAGGAAUUUUUCAGUGCCAUUAUAAUCUUAUGGAACCAUUGUUUCAUAUGCAUGCAGUUUGCUGUUGAUCAAAAUGUAGUUAAGCAGCACAUGGCUGUAAUUAAAACACUAUUGUUUGUUAUAAUAGAAAAUAAAAUUUUUCUUUUUAGCCUCUGUAUUAAUAAAGAGCACUAGAAAGUACUUUGUUUAUCAGAUAAUGAAUAUGUUUGACAGAUGUACAUACGUAUUUAUCAAAUGAAUCUUUUUUUGUGGGGGAAACCUUAACUAAGAAUAGGCCUGUGUUUUAAAAUGGCUGCCUGGAGGACAAGUGCUAUAAGGAAAUUUCAGUGGUAUUUGCUUGACCUGGCAUUAAGUGGGGGGAAAAACAAGCCCCAGGUGAAUUGAUAGAUGGAUGUCUGAACAUGUUCAGGAAUGAUGUUUUGAACAAUGUUUGCCUCCUGUGUCAUGUAGGCAGAGAGAUGAUAAAAGUUUUUUUCCCCUCUUGAUACCAGGUAAUUCUGAUACCGACUACCAGAAGUUAGCUUCAGACUCCGCAGGUUGAAGGGCUUUGUCCCAUAAGACCAUUCUUACUUCAGACACCAAUUGCAAUGAUCAGUUAUCAGGUCCCAAGGUUACCUACACUUAUGUCUGAUUUGGCUACAAAAUUGGAGGUUCCCACAGUCUACCCCUUCAGAUUUGAUAACUUUCUAAUAUGGCUGCAAAAAACUCAGAGAAAUACUUAUGUUUAUCAGUUUUUUAUAAAGGAUACAAUUAGCCAGAUGAGGAGAUAGAUAGGGCAAAGUCCAGGAGGGUCCUGAGUGUUGAGUGUAGGAGUCUCUGUCCUGUGGAAUAUGCCACCGUCCCAGCAUGUAGAUGUAUUCACCAAUCAGGAAGCUCUCUGAGCCCUUUUGUGUAGUUGUUUUUAUGGAGGUCUCAUUAUGUAGGCAGGAUUGAUUAAAUCAUUGACAGUGGGUGAUUUGCUCAAGCCCCUCUCCCCUCAUCAGAAGUUGGUGGGUGGUACUGAAAGUUCUGAACUUCUGGUCAAGGCUUUGUCUUUCUAGGUAGCCCUCAUCCUGAAGCUAUCUAGGGGCUUUCCAAGAGUUGUCUUAUUAGAACAAAGAACACUCCUAUCACCCUUAUCACUCAGGAAAUUCCAAGGGUUUUAGGAGCUGUAUGCCAGGAACCUGGGACAGACCAAGUAUCUUUCUGUGAUACCACAGAAUGGGACCCCAAAAGCCAGCUCCAGCUGGUGUCUAGUGCCUUUAGUUGGGCACUGGAUAUCGGUUACAGGGCAUAAGUGGCCCAGUGGGGUUGCCGUUUAACCCAUCUCUGCUGUAUUAACCUCAUGUACCUUAGCUCAUGGCUAGGUCGUUUCAAGUCUCACCUAAUGUCAGUUGUUUCAUCCUUCUCUGGAUGCAUGUUCACUUCUGGAAUAGGUGAAUAUCUGGGCCACUAUGUUUGCUGUCAUCCUGAGCAAACUUCCAGCUUAGAAACCAGCUUUAUGGAAUCAUCCCAGAGCCUUUAUUUUAUUUUAUUUUAUUUUAUUUUAUUUAUUUAUUUAUUUAUUUUUUGAGGCAGAGUCUUGCUCUGUAGCCCAGGCUGAAAUGCAGUGGCAAAGUCAUGGCUCACUGCAGCUUCAACCUCCCAGGCUCAAGCAAUCCUUCCGUUUCAGCCUCCCAAGUAGCUGAGAUUACAGGUGUGUACCACGACACCUGGCUGAUUUAAAACCUUUUGUAGAGAUAGUGUCCCAGUGUGUUUGCCCAGGCUGGUCUCAGACUCCUGGGGUUAAGCGAUCCUCUUGCCUCAGCCUCCCAAAAUGUUGGGAUUACGGGCGUGAGCCACUGAACUUGGUCCCAGAGCCUUUUAGAACAGUGUUGAGUUGCCCUUUAUUUGCACCAGGGCUAAGGCAGUAGAAAAAAAAUGUUUAUGGGCCAUGUUUUUCUUCCUAGUCAAAAUAAAAAUAGCCAUGUAAUCUAUGGAGGCAGCAGAUAUGUUGUUAGUAUACACUAGAAGUCAGGAAAUUCGUACUGCCUUUCAGCUGCUAAAGUACUGGGACAUAUUUGAGAAGCAGUAAUGCAGAGGCAGCUGUCUGAUCUUUGAUCUCUGAUAAUGCUUAUUUCAUUGCAUCCCUGAAACCACCCUGCAAAGGAUUUAUCAUCUUUGCUGCUUUGCAUAUGGAAUAGCAUAGGCCCAGAGAGACGUAGCUUGACUGCAAUCACAUGGUGAGUUAGUUGUAGCUUCUGCAAAUGUACAGAACUAAGAAGCUACUUUUCUUGUGUGUUAUUCUAGUGAUGAUGGUCAUUAUAAUUGAUGUACCUGAUAUUAUGCUAGGUUUAGGGAUACAGAAAUGAAAGAAGAUCACAGUCCCUCAUCUGGGACCUCUGUUUUUUUGGUGUCACCUCUCUGCAUAGACAGUUCUGCAGUAUUGAUGCUGCUGUUCUGGUUGAUCCUUCUGUCAUGCCUGCACCAUCUUUUCUGCCAGACUGAAGUGUUCUUGCUUGGGGAAAAGCAGAUUUGCAAAGGUUCUCUUUUUCCUGAUUGUUGCUUUGCAGAUUGAGUAUAUUUGUUUGUUUGUUUUUAAGUGAACAAAAGUUGAAUGAGAUUGAUUACUGGCUCUUUAAAGAAUAAUUACUCCCCCUUUUGACUUAUGUAGCAUCUUGAGGUGAUCUAUGACCGUUUGUACUUGUCAUGACUUCCAUUAGAUUAAACUCUGGGGCAAAGACGUUGCUCUUCAUUGUGCUCAUAUGACACCAUUACUGCCAGUGGAAUUGAAAUAAAUUGAGUAAGGGCGAGUGUUUCCUAACAAAUGUUAUCCUGGGCCUGAGGAACCAUCAUCAAGAUGGAGUGGCCCUGCGAUUAAUUUUGGACUUAAAGCAAAAAACAAACAAAUUUUUUUCUUUAAAUAACCAGUUGGCACAGAUACAGAAUAAAAUAAGAUAGAUCCACGUGUAGUUUUUGAAAAUUUAGGUCAGGUGGCUCACUCCUAUAAUCCCAGCACUUUGGGAGGCCAAGGCGUGUGGAUAACUCGAGGUUAGGAGUUUAAGACCAGUCUGGCCAUCAUGAUGAAACCCCAUCUCUACUAAAAGUACAAAAAUUAGCUGGGCAUGGUGGCGCAUGCCUGUAAACCUAGCUACUCAGGAGGCUAAGGCAGGAGAAUUGCUUGAACCUGGUAGGCGGUAGUUGCAAUGAGCCGAGAUUGCGCCACUGCACUCCAGCCUGGGUGACAGAGUGAGACUCUGUCUCAAAAGAAAAAAAAAUUUAAGAAAUAAUCAUCAGUGUAUAUCUUCCUUUUUUCAUUUUUCUUUAAAAAAAAAAACAACCCUUGUAUGCAUAGCUGAAGGAGAAAUAAUUGAAAGUGUUUAUAAGAUUUCAAGGUGAUGGGCUGGACACAGUUGCUCAUGCCUAAUAAUCUGCACGCCUGUAAUCCCAGCUAUUCGGGAGCCUGAGGCAGGAGAAUCACUUGAACCCAGGAGGCAGAGGUUGCAGUGGGCCGAGAUAGUGCCAUUGCACUCUAGCCUGGGCGACAAAGGUGAAACUCCAUCUCAAAUAAAAAAAAAGAUUUCAAGGUGAUGGGUUUCAUGUGGACCAAUUUUAUCCUUCCCUGAUGAUAAUUUGACAUAUGAGUCAGAUAUUUUCCUAAUUUUCGUAAUUCGAGUGGGAUUGUGUGUUUGUUUGUUUGUUUUGAGACAGGGUCUCACUCUGUUGUUCAGGCUGGAGUGCAGUAGGCCAGUCAUGGCUCACUGUAGCCUUGGCUUCUCAGGCUCAAGUGAGCCUCCCACCUCAGCCUCUUAAGUAGCUGGGACUAUAGGUGCGUGCUCCCACACCUGGCUAAUUUUUUCUGUUUUUUUUUGUAGAGACAAGGUCUCAUUAUAUUGCCGAGGCUGGGACUCCUGAGCUCAAGUAAUCCUCCUACCUUGGUCUCCUAAAGUGCUGGGAUUAUAUCCACGAGCCACCACACCCAGCCUCGCAUGAGAUUUUAACAGAGCAAAGUACCUGUUGGAAAUCUUGCGCACAAAGCCUCCUUUAUUCUGUUAUUCCCACUGACAGGAAUUCAGAUACCUGGAUCAAUUCUGUUUCGGUUUUGCUAAAAUCUCUAACUUGAUAUUUUACUUUUCUAAAAACCUGUAUUAUCAAUGAAAUGGAAUUAGGAAAACAGGACCUAUAGAAGUUAAGACCUCUUCAAUCUAUUGAUGUUUCAUGGUGCCUUUUAUAUUCAAAAUGCUUUGUUCUCACAAAAAUAAUACUUUUUGUUUGGAGAAAAAGGCUGUGGGGUGUGUGUGUGUGUGUGUGUGUGUGUUUUCCUCUCAAAGAUAGCAGUAAAAUAAACUCCUUCUGACAAAGGCUUCUUAAAAGAAAGGAGAAAAAAAAACCUUCCUGCUAAUUGUGUUCUUUAAAAUCCUGAUUCCCCGUUUUACUUUCUGGAUGUGUAUUCUGGGCUUUUUCAAUGUCAACCAAUACUCUCUUGAUGGGAAAUUCAGCUGGAUUUGGGUAUGUUCAUUGGGUUUUCCUAGAACAGUUUGAAGAUCCAUCUCAUUUACCUAAACAAAUAUUCCUUAUAAUUAUUAUGAAAAUUGGGCCUGUUAUAGACUAAUAAUUGACUUAAACCAUACAGGGUUAUGUUUGUCAGUAUCUCGUGAGUCAGCUUUUCUAGGGGCAGAGAUUGAAGAGUUAGUUCUGAGAUUGAAUACUAUUUAUCAGGGUUUUGUUUUGUGUACCUUAUUCUCCUGUAACCACCUGGUUGGCUUUUAUCAUAGAUACAUUUUUGGGAAACAGGCAACCACAUGGUUAAUGAAGAUAGAGAAGACGUGAAAUUUGUUACCUUUAUAGAUUUUUUCCCCUUGCCCUGUUCUCAUUCUUCUCAUUUGCCUAAAAAAAAAUAUAAGGAGGCCGGGUGCGGUGGCUCACGCCUGUAAUCCCAGCACUGAGGCAGGCAGAUCACCUGAGCUCAGGAGUUCGAGACCAGCCUGGCCAACGUGGCGAAACUCCGUCUCUACUGAAAAUACAAAAAUUAGCCGGGCGUGGUAGUCCCAGCUACUGCAGGUACCUGAGGCAGGAGAAUUGCUUGAGCCUGAGAGGCAGAGGUUGCAAUGAGCCGAGAUUGUGUGCCAUUGCAUUCCAGCCUGGGUGACAAAGCAAGACUCUGUCUCAAAAAAAAAAAAAAAAGUAUAAGGAGUAUUCACAUUUCUAUGAGAUCUGUAAAUUUAGGUUAGAAAAUUUAGUUAACUGUGUUUUGUAAUAGUCAUAUAAAUAAGCACAAAGACCCUCCAGACUUCUUCCCAGCAUGUGACAGUGGAAGAAAGGGGUAAUAAAGUAGAUUUUUUUGUUACUCUCAUUGGUAAAAAUAAGUCUGUCCAUGGGAAGGUUAACACUGAGUUUACCAUCUUGAUGAUUCCAUAUGGUUCCUAGCAAUUCUAAUCUCAAAGUUGGUUGGCAGAAUGUUUAGGUCUUUGGGUAGAAUAUCUUCUGUGCCUUUUCUGUGAAUUGUAAAAUUACAUUUGGGAAAUAAAGAAAAAAAUCCCUGAUUAUCCCACUAUAGCAAUACAACCACUGUAAACAUUUUGGUAUACAGUUGUGUUGCAUUAUAUGCAUUUUCUGAUUUUUGUAUGUCCACCUGUGCUUAUUUGAACUGUAUCCCCCUCCCCACUUCCCACACCCUGUUUUCUCACUCCUGGAGUGAGCAUGGGCAGUGGGGAUGAGACUCGCCUGUGGCUUCAGUUUGUCUCCUUUUCUAAGUUUCUCUGAGUGGGCAUUCACUGUGCUGGCUGUGAUUCUGUUAUUUAAAGCAAUAUAUUUUCAUACCUUAUGGCCCUUAAAUGCAAGCCAACCUCUUCAUCUGGUGUCAACCAAAGGAAAAGUGAUCUGUUGCAGCGCUGGAGGAAAAACUGGCAAUGUUGGACUUACCUAAAUUGAAAGAUGGUUACGACUAUGGCUAUGUCUGCGUGGAGUUUUCACUCUUGGAAGAUGCCAUCGGAUGCAUGGAGGCCAACCAGGGAACUCUAAUGAUCCAGGACAAAGAAGUUACCCUGGAGUAUGUAUCAAGCCUGGAUUUUUGGUACUGCAAACGAUGUAAGGCAAACAUUGGUGGGCACCGAUCUUCCUGUUCAUUCUGCAAGAACCCAAGAGAAGUGACAGAGGCCAAGCAAGAAUUAAUAACCUACCCUCAGCCUCAGAAAACAUCCAUACCAGCACCAUUGGAAAAACAGCCCAACCAGCCCCUAAGACCAGCUGAUAAGGAACCUGAACCCAGGAAGAGGGAAGAAGGCCAAGAGUCACGCUUAGGACAUCAAAAGAGAGAAGCAGAAAGGUAUCUGCCUCCUUCUCGAAGGGAAGGGCCAACUUUCCGAAGAGACCGAGAGAGGGAGUCAUGGUCUGGAGAGACACGCCAGGAUGGAGAGAGCAAAACUAUCAUGCUAAAGCGUAUCUAUCGUUCCACACCACCUGAGGUGAUAGUGGAAGUGCUGGAGCCCUAUGUCCGCCUUACUACUGCCAACGUCCGUAUCAUCAAGAACAGAACAGGCCCUAUGGGGCAUACCUAUGGCUUUAUUGACCUCGACUCCCAUGCGGAAGCUCUUCGUGUGGUGAAGAUCUUACAGAACCUUGAUCCGCCAUUUAGCAUUGAUGGGAAGAUGGUAGCUGUAAACCUGGCCACUGGAAAACGAAGAAAUGAUUCUGGGGACCAUUCUGACCACAUGCAUUACUAUCAGGGUAAAAAAUAUUUCCGAGAUAGGAGGGGAGGUGGCAGAAAUUCAGACUGGUCUUCAGAUACAAAUCGACAAGGACAACAGUCAUCAUCUGACUGCUACAUAUAUGAUUCUGCUACUGGCUACUAUUAUGACCCCUUGGCAGGAACUUAUUAUGACCCCAAUACCCAGCAAGAAGUCUAUGUGCCCCAGGAUCCUGGAUUACCUGAGGAAGAAGAGAUCAAGGAAAAAAAACCCACCAGUCAAGGAAAGUCAAGUAGCAAGAAGGAAAUGUCUAAAAGAGAUGGCAAGGAGAAAAAAGACAGAGGAGUGACGAGGUUUCAGGAAAAUGCCAGUGAAGGGAAGGCCCCUGCAGAAGACGUCUUUAAGAAGCCCCUGCCUCCUACUGUGAAGAAGGAAGAGAGUCCCCCUCCACCUAAAGUGGUAAACCCACUGAUCGGCCUCUUGGGUGAAUAUGGAGGAGACAGUGACUAUGAGGAGGAAGAAGAGGAGGAACAGACCCCUCCCCCACAGCCCCGCACAGCACAGCCCCAGAAGCGAGAGGAGCAAACCAAGAAGGAGAAUGAAGAAGACAAACUCACUGACUGGAAUAAACUGGCUUGUCUGCUUUGCAGAAGGCAGUUUCCCAAUAAAGAAGUUCUGAUCAAACACCAGCAGCUGUCAGACCUGCACAAGCAAAACCUGGAAAUCCACCGGAAGAUAAAACAGUCUGAGCAGGAGCUAGCCUAUCUGGAAAGGAGAGAACGAGAGGGAAAGUUUAAAGGAAGAGGAAAUGAUCGCAGGGAAAAGCUCCAGUCUUUUGACUCUCCAGAAAGGAAACGGAUUAAGUACUCCAGGGAAACUGACAGUGAUCGUAAACUUGUUGAUAAAGAAGAUAUCGACACUAGCAGCAAAGGAGGCUGUGUCCAACAGGCUACUGGCUGGAGGAAAGGGACAGGCCUGGGAUAUGGCCAUCCUGGAUUGGCUUCAUCAGAGGAGGCUGAAGGCCGGAUGAGGGGCCCCAGUGUUGGAGCCUCAGGAAGAACCAGCAAAAGACAGUCCAACGAGACUUACCGAGAUGCUGUUCGAAGAGUCAUGUUUGCUCGAUAUAAAGAACUCGAUUAAGAAAGGAGACAAGUUCCAUGGGAUACAACCUCCCUCUUGUUUUGUUUGUCUCUCCUUUUCUUUUGUUACUGUUCUUGCUGCUAGAACUUUUUUAAAUAAACUUUUUUUCAAUGUGA